GCCGGCGCGCCCCUGGGAGGGUGAGCCGGCGCCGGGCCCAGGCCCGGACCUGGUGGGAGGCGGGGGGAGGUGGGGACGAGGCCUGGGGAGGCGGGCCCCGCCCAUCUGCAGGUGGCUGUGAACGCUGAGCGGCUCCAGGCGGGGGCCGGGCCCGGGGGCGGGGUCUGUGGCGCGCGUCCCCGCCACGUGUCCCCGGUCACCGGCCCUGCCCCCGGGCCCUGUGCUUAUAACCUGGGAUGGGCACCCCUGCCAGUCCUGCUCUGCCGCCUGCCACCGCUGCCCGAGCCCGAGUGGUUCACUGCACUGUGAAAACAGAUUCCAGACGCCGGGAACUCACGCCUCCAAUCCCAGACGCUAUGUCCAGCAAAGGCUCCGUGGUUCUGGCCUACAGUGGCGGCCUGGACACCUCGUGCAUCCUCGUGUGGCUGAAGGAACAAGGCUAUGACGUCAUUGCCUAUCUGGCCAACAUUGGCCAGAAGGAAGACUUCGAGGAAGCCAGGAAGAAGGCACUGAAGCUUGGGGCCAAAAAGGUGUUCAUUGAGGAUGUCAGCAGGGAGUUUGUGGAGGAGUUCAUCUGGCCGGCCAUCCAGUCCAGCGCACUGUAUGAGGACCGCUACCUCCUGGGCACCUCUCUUGCCAGGCCCUGCAUCGCCCGCAAACAAGUGGAAAUCGCCCAGCGGGAGGGGGCCAAGUAUGUGUCCCACGGCGCCACAGGAAAGGGGAACGAUCAGGUCCGGUUUGAGCUCAGCUGCUACUCACUGGCCCCCCAGAUAAAGGUCAUUGCUCCCUGGAGGAUGCCUGAAUUCUACAACCGGUUCAAGGGCCGCAAUGACCUGAUGGAGUACGCAAAGCAACACGGGAUUCCCAUCCCGGUCACUCCCAAGAACCCGUGGAGCAUGGAUGAGAACCUCAUGCACAUCAGCUACGAGGCUGGAAUCCUGGAGAACCCCAAGAACCAAGCGCCUCCAGGUCUCUACACGAAGACCCAGGACCCAGCCAAAGCCCCCAACACCCCUGACAUUCUCGAGAUCGAGUUCAAAAAAGGGGUCCCUGUGAAGGUGACCAACGUCAAGGAUGGCACCACCCACCAGACCUCCUUGGAGCUCUUCAUGUACCUGAACGAAGUCGCGGGCAAGCAUGGCGUGGGCCGUAUUGACAUCGUGGAGAACCGCUUCAUUGGAAUGAAGUCCCGAGGUAUCUACGAGACCCCAGCAGGCACCAUCCUUUACCAUGCUCAUUUAGACAUCGAGGCCUUCACCAUGGACCGGGAAGUGCGCAAAAUCAAACAAGGCCUGGGCUUGAAAUUUGCUGAGCUGGUGUAUACCGGUUUCUGGCACAGCCCUGAGUGUGAAUUUGUCCGCCACUGCAUCGCCAAGUCCCAGGAGCGAGUGGAAGGGAAAGUGCAGGUGUCCGUCCUCAAGGGCCAGGUGUACAUCCUCGGCCGGGAGUCCCCACUGUCUCUCUACAAUGAGGAGCUGGUGAGCAUGAACGUGCAGGGUGAUUAUGAGCCAACUGAUGCCACCGGGUUCAUCAACAUCAAUUCCCUCAGGCUGAAGGAAUAUCAUCGUCUCCAGAGCAAGGUCACUGCCAAAUAGACCCGUGUACAAUGAGGAGCUGGGGCCUCCUCAAUUUGCAGAUCCCCCAAGUACAGGCGCUAAUUGUUGUGAUAAUUUGUAAUUGUGACUUGUUCUCCCCGGCUGGCAGCGUAGUGGGGCUGCCAGGCCCCAGCUUUGUUCCCUGGUCCCCCUGAAGCCUGCAAACGUUGUCAUCGAAGGGAAGGGUGGGGGGCAGCUGCGGUGGGGAGCUAUAAAAAUGACAAUUAAAAGAGACACUAGUCUUUUAUUUCUA